AUUCCGGCCCAUUUCCACCCCCGGAGCUCUCACCCCUCCAGUGCCGACGGUAGCGAAAGACUUUCCUCCAGGGGCUUCCUCACUGGGGAAUUGCCGGAAAGAGCAAACAAAAAAGGCGCUGGUGUAGGCUCCAAAAUAAACACAUCUGAAUUCAUGAUGGCAUCGACAGAGGCUCUUAUUGGAUUAAAAGUUUCAAAACAAACAAUAACGCUUUGGAAAAAGGGUUGAAUGCACCCUCAGGCACGACCAUGGAGAAAGGUGGGAACAUACAAUUGGAGAUUCCUGACUUCAGCAACUCUGUCCUGAGCCAUCUAAACCAGUUGCGCAUGCAGGGCCGUCUCUGUGAUAUUGUGGUCAAUGUGCAAGGACAAGCUUUUCGGGCUCACAAAGUGGUGCUGGCUGCCAGCUCCCCCUAUUUCCGGGAUCACAUGUCCUUGAAUGAGAUGAGUACAGUCUCCAUUUCAGUCAUCAAGAACCCUACUGUUUUUGAACAGCUCCUUUCUUUCUGUUACACAGGGCGGAUAUGCCUGCAACUGGCAGAUAUCAUCAGCUACCUAACAGCUGCCAGUUUUCUGCAAAUGCAGCAUAUUAUAGACAAAUGUACACAGAUCCUGGAGGGCAUUCAUUUCAAAAUUAAUGUGGCUGAGGUUGAAGCAGAAUUAAGUCAAACAAGGACAAAGCAUCAAGAGAGACCUCCAGAGUCUCACAGGGUUACACCAAAUCUCAACCGCUCCCUUAGCCCACGACAUAAUACCCCAAAGGGAAACCGGCGAGGUCAGGUUAGUGCUGUGCUGGAUAUCAGAGAGCUAAGUCCUCCUGAGGAGUCCACCAGCCCUCAGAUCAUUGAACCAAGUUCUGAUGUAGAGAGCCGGGAGCCCAUUCUUCGGAUCAACCGAGCAGGACAGUGGUAUGUGGAGACAGGAGUGGCGGACCGUGGGGGUCGGAGUGAUGAUGAAGUUAGAGUUCUUGGAGCAGUACACAUCAAAACUGAAAAUCUGGAGGAGUGGCUUGGGCCUGAGAAUCAGCCUUCUGGAGAAGAUGGGAGUAGUGCAGAGGAAGUAACAGCCAUGGUGAUUGAUACCACAGGCCAUGGUUCUGUAGGACAGGAAAAUUAUACUUUAGGGUCUUCAGGAGCCAAGGUGGCUCGGCCAACAAGCAGUGAAGUUGACAGAUUUAGCCCCUCCGGCAGUGUUGUUCCCUUGACAGAGAGACACAGAGCCAGAAGUGAGUCUCCUGGGAGAAUGGAUGAGCCUAAGCAACCCAGCUCCCAGGUAUGGAGUUGUGGAUUUAGAACUGCUUUGGUGGUUGGAGGAAUUGCUACUGUGUAUGAAUAGAAAAUAAUGAAAAAGAAAAGAUGUAGGAGAGGUAACAAUGGCCCUGUUAAAGAAAUACUGUAUUUUUUUUCCCUGAGGGUAGCAGAAGUUUAAUAUUAAAAUUAUACAGAGACAUCACCAGAAAGGAAAAUUGCAGACUGGUAUUUCUACCAAGCAUAGAUGCAAAUAUUUUGAAAAGAACAUUAACAAAUUAACACUGAUAGCUGGUUUAACAUUUUAAAAUUAAUCAUUGUAAUCUGUUUCAUUAAUAAGGAAAAAGUGAUAAAUUACAUGUGGCAAUUUUGAUAAAUACAGAAAAGAACAAUUGGCUAAAACUCUUAGCAAACUAGAAAUACAAGGGAACUGGCCGGGCGCAGUGGCUCGCGCCUGUAAUCCCAGCACUUUGGGAGGCCGAGGCAGGUGGAUCACCUGAGGUCCGGAGUUCGAGACCAGCUUGACCAACAUGGAGAAAACCCGUCUCUACUAAAAAUACAAAAUUACCCAGGCAUGGUGGCACGUGCCCGUGAUCCCAACUACUCCAGAGGCUGAGGCAGGACAAUGGCUUGAACCCGGGAGGCGGAGGUUGCUGUGAGCCGAGAUCACACCAUUGCACUCCAGCCUGGGCCACAAGAGUGAAACUCCGUCUCAAAAAAAAAAAAAAAAAAGAAAUACAAGGGAACUUUCUUAAUCUGAUUGAAAGUAUCUAUCUAAAAAAUCUAUAGAAAACAUCUUUUUUUUUUUUUUGAGACGGAGUCUCGAGUCUCACCCUGUCGCCCAGGCUGGAGUGCAUGGAGUGCAGUGGUGCAAUCUCGGCUCACUGCAAGCUCCACCUCCCGGGUUCACGCCAUUCUCCUGCCUCAGCCUCCCAAGUAGCUGGGACUACAGGCACCUGCCACCACGCCCGGCUAAUUAUUUGUAUUUUUGAGUAGAGACGGGGUUUCACCGUGUUAGCCAGGGUGGUUUCGAUCUCCUGACCUCAUGAUCCGCCUGCCUCGGCCUCCCAAAAUGCUGGGAUUACAGGUGUGAGCCACUGCACCCAGCCACUGCACCCAGCCCAGAAAACAUCUUAAUAGUAAAUUAUUGAAAGCUUCCUUCGUGUGAUUGGGAAUGAGACAGAAUGUCUGCUACCACCACUUCUACCCAGCUUUUUAUUUGUAGUCCUAGUCAAUGCAAUAAAGCAAGAAAUACAAAUUUAUAGCAUAAGGAUGACAAAGCAAGAAAUAGAACUUUUGUUAUUAGUAGACAGCCUGACUUGUUAUGUAAAAAAUGCAAAGUUAAAUACUGUAUUUGAUUACUUUUUUUUUAAAAUUCUUGCUUGUGGGCGUGCAGGAAAAUACACUUUCGAUGUCAGCAGAGUUUGGGAAAUAUAAAAAAGUAAGAUUGUGGAACUCUUUCCUGAUUAUAAUAACCACACUGUAGACCUGAUAGUAAUAAAAAAUAAUCCCAGAAAACCACAUACAGGUAAUUUGCAGGUAAUUUAGGACCUGGAAUCGAAAGUCUGAUUAUUAUGUGUGUGUGUGUGUGUGUGUGUGUGUGUGUGUGUGUGUGUGUGCACGUGUGUACUGUAUAUACUAUAUGUAGUAUACACACACUAUGUAUACUAUAGUAUGCACACACUAUAUAUACUAUAUAUACUAUGCGUAGUAUACACACACACACAGUUAUGAAGUUACUAAUUUGUAGCAUUUUAUUUAUAUAUAUAUGUGUGCAUAUAUAUAUAUAUUUUUUUUUUUUUUUGAGGCAGUCUUGCUCUGUCACCCAGGCUGGAGUGCAGUGGUGUGAUCUCGGCUCGCUGCAAUCUCUGCCUCCUGGGUUCAAACGGUUCUCCUGCCUCAACCUCCUGAGUAGCUGGGAUUACAGGCGCCCGCCAGCACACCUAGCUAAUUUUUGUAUUUUUAGUAGAUAGCAGGGUUUCACCAUGUGGGCCAGGCUGGUCUUGAACUCCUGAACUCAGGUGAUCCACCCACCUCAGCCUCCGAAAGUGCUGGGAUUGCAGAUGUGAGCCACCGCGCCCGGCCUGCAUUAUAUAUUUGUAAACAAAUUGCUUAUGCUUUUUUUUUUCUGAGACAGGGUCUCACUCUGGUUGACCAGGUUGCAUUGCACUGGUGCGAUCUCAACUCACUUUAGCCUCAACCUCCUAGGUUCAGGUGAUUCUCUCCCCUCAGCCUCCUGAGUAGCUGGAACCACAGAUGCGCACUACCAUGCCCAGCUGAUUUUUUUGUGUGUUUUUAGUGGAAAUGGCGUUGCACCAGUUUGCCCAGGCUGGUCUCAAACUCUUGGACUCAAGCAAUCUGCCUGCCUCAGCCUCCCAAUUUGCUGGGAUUACAGGCGUGAGCCACUGUGCCCAGCUGCUUACACAUUUUUAUGUGUGUUUGCUAUUUCAUGUACUGUAUCUUGUCAUUUAUUUUCUUCCUGAAUAUUUUGUUAGACUAACACAUUCUAGAAAGGAUAGGAAUGAUGGGUUUUUUUCUAUUUUCUUUGCAACUCUCCUUAGCAACUAGUAUGAGUUUGCUCAUUUUUUUUUUCUCACAGGUCUGAUUGAAUGAUUUUUUUUAAAGCUCAUGAACUCACCAAGUAGAAGACAAUAAAUUGUGAACAUUUUUGCCUUUAAAAAGUAAACACUGUUGAAUUAAGAUUACAUAGCUCAUGUUUCUAGCCUCUGCAUUACACUGAUAGUAUCUUGUCUAAUUUUUAACUAAACCACUGAAUUAUUAUUACUUUUUUUUUUAGAUGGAGUCUGGCUCUGUCAUCCAGGCUGGAGUGCAGUGGCGCAGCCUUGGCUCACUGCAACCUCCACCUCUCUGGUUCGAGCAAUUCUCCUGUCUCAGCUUCCCGAGUAGCUGGGACUACAGGUGCAUGCUACCACGCCCAGCUAAUUUUUGUAUUUUUAGUAGAGACAGGGUUUCACCAUAUUGGUCAGGCUGGUCUCAAACUCCUGACCUCAGGUAAUCCAACCGCCUCAGCCUCCCGAAGUGCUGGGAUUACAGACAUGAGCCACCGUACCCAGCCUAAACCACUGAAUAUUUAUUGUGUGCAUGGUAUAGUAAUAGCCGUAAGACAUUGUUACAAACUGUGUUUUUUAGUUUUGAUAAGAUGUUAGAGAAAAUAUUAGGAGCUUGGAGGAAAGGUAAUUUGGCUCAUAUUAUUAGGGCCCUUUUUCUCCUCAUCUCUCAAAUAUGGUAUGAUAGCAAUGCAGAGGAGGCUGUUGAGCAGAUAUAGGCGUGUGUCACUAAUUGACAGUAUAUUCUGAGAAAUGCUAGACCAUUUUGUCAUUGUGCAAAUAUAGAGUAUAUUUACACAAAUUUAGAUGGUAUAACCUACUGCACACCUAGUUCAUAUGAUAUAUCCCGUUCCUCCUAGGCUGCAAACCUGUAUAGCAUGUUACUGUACUGAAUACUGUAGGCAGUUACAAAGUAAAUAUUUGUGUAUCUAAACAUAAAUUACUGAAUAUAGUAAAUAUUUGUGUAUCUAAACAUAGAAACGAUAGUGUAAAAAUAUUGUAUUAUAAUCGUAUGGAAGCACGGUUACAUAUGUGGUCCAUCACUGACCAAAAUGUUAUGUGGUACAUAACUGUAAAUUCAGUAAUGAGUCAGACGUUACAACUUAAUGGGGGCAUAAGACAGACUAACAAAUACACACAAAAAAACUGUAAGACUCUACAGUAUAAACUUGAGUAAUAGUGUUGUGGGACUAGGAUUGUUUAAAAGGCAAUGGAAUAAUGAAAUCAGUGUCCACUUAAGGAAAGUGUUGUCAAGAUUUUCUUUCUUUUUUUUUUUUUUUUUUUUUUUUCCGAGACAGGAUCUCACUUUGUCGUCCAGGCUAGAGUGCAGUGGUAUGAUCAUGUCUCACUGCAGCCUUGCCUUCCCUGGCUCAAGCAGUCCCCUCACCUCAGCUCCUGAGUAGCUGGGACCACUGGCAUGUGCCACCACACCCGGUUAAUUUUUUUGUUUUUUGUAGACACAGGGUUUCACUGUGUUGCCCAGGCUGAUCUCGAAUUCCUGAGCUCAGUAGUGGCUCACGCCUGUAAUCCCAUCACUUGGAAGACCAAGGUGCAGUCCUCCCACCUUGGUCUCCCAAGGGGUGAGACUACAGAUGUGAGCCACCACAUACAGCCUCAAGGAUAGGGUAAUAUAUAUGCCUUAAUGGAUAUGAAAGUUUAAUAUGGUAAGUCUACUCACCAGUUUUUUUCCUCUACUACAGAGAACUAAAACAGGGCAAGGACUUACAGUAAGAAUGAAUAUUGAUAGAUUUGAAGAACUUCCUGAUUAUGGGGGUGAUUAAACUGGAACACACUAAUAAAGUUACUCUUUUACUUGAAAACAUUCUGUAGCUUUUUCUAUGACAUGAAGGUUAAUAUACUUGGCCUAAUUUUUCAAGUGAUUUACAGUCUUUUUAACCCAACUUUUCCCACCACUCAUCAGCAUUCACUGUCUCAAACAGAUAGACUCUCCCUGUGUCAGAACCACAUUAAACUAUUUCUCUUUCUGCAUCUAAAGUCUGAAUGCCUCAUUUCUUUUCAGGUGUCUGGGUUCAGCCAAGGUCCAGCUCCUAGUUUUAUCUGUCCUAACUGCUCCAGUCCUCUUUGAUUUUUCCUUUUUAGGCUACUAUUAUAGCAUGGUACAAUACAAUUUUUCCUAAUUCUCUAGACUCAAUAUAUGUUGUUCCUUUUUUAUUUGCAUUAGUUUUGUGUCUCCUGUUAAACUGAAAUCUCCUUGAGAGCAGAGACCACAUUUUCUUUCCUCUUUUUGUUUUUGUCUUUUGACAGUUUUAGUACCAAUAAGUCUUUGUUUAUGCAUUCUAUUUUCCCAGGGAAAGGAGAAGGGAAGGAAGGGGAAAGAGUCAGCCUAUGUUACAGAAUGAUUAGAAAAUGGGCAAGGAAGUACCCAGUACAGCACAAUCAACCAUCAAAUAAACACACCCCAGUGAUGGGGUCACCAAUGCCCAAAGAGGCUCUGUCUCCUGCAGUUCAGGAAUAAGGGGAAGAGACCAGGAAAAGAACAGAUAGGUACAGACUUUCCUACCCUCCCUUCCACCUCAUAAAUUCAAGAUUUCACAUAAAGCUUUAGCUUCUAGUGGUAAACAUUAAGUUACAUUUGUUCAUCUCCUGUUAAGCAAUCUUGUGGCUACUUUGACAUAAAUUUCUUACACCUGUAUAAAAGUUCUUGAGUGACUUGGAUAUAAAUUCAACAUUUAGGCUGGGCGCAGUGGCUCAUGCCUAUAAUCCCAGCACUUUGGGAGGCUGAGAUGGGCGGAUCACUUGACAUCAGGAGUGAGGUUCAAGACAAGCCUGGCUAACAUGGUGAAACCCCUUCUCUAAUAAAAAUACAAAAACAUUAGCCAGGCAUGGUGGCGGGUGCCUGUAAUCCCAGAUACUUGGGAGGCUGAGACAGGAGAAUCGUUUGAACCCGGGAGGUGGAGGUUGCAGUGAGCCGAGACCAUGCCAUUGCCCUCCAGCCCGGGGAACAAGAGCAAAACUCCAUCUCAAAAAAAAAAAAAAAAAAUCAGCAUUUAUUCUCUUUCUUGGCUUCCUGACCCCACUUUCUACAUGGAAAGCCCCCAGUUGCUUCUCUCUACUUUAGGAUUAAAGAUGAGGUAGGUUUAAUCCAUCCAGAAUCCAGCAGUGUCUUAAGGGUUUAGCAUGAAUCACAUCAAGAAAAAUGGUCUUGACUCAGGAGAUUGGAAACAAGGGAUGGGGGUUUCCUAGCUUCUUCAGGAUUUUUGCAUCAAUCAUUUCAGAGUUGUGUAGUUGCCCUAAAAAUUAAAUAUGUAUAUGCGUGGGUGUGUAGGUUUUCUUUUGGGGGUCGAUGGAAAAGAGGGAGAAGGGUAGGAGACAAAUUUUUAGGACAGAAGAUCUGGCCCAAUAGGUAAUAGGGAAAGGAGAAAACUAAAGAAAGGAUGGUUCAAGAUCCCCACUUUUAAGAAGAGGGCUCCGCAGUCUAAUGUUUCAGAUUUUUUGCCAGGUACAGAACCUUCUGUCAAAGAUGUUUUGGCUAUUUUUCUCUCAAUACAAAAAGAAGUUUGUAAACCCCAAAAGAACACGGAGAAGUAGUUUGCAACUAUCGGCUGGGCGAGGUGGCUCACACUUGUAAUCCCAGCACUUUGGGAGGCCCAGGUAUGUGGAUCACCUGAGGUCAUGAGUUCAAGACCAGCCUGGCCAACAUGGUGAAACCCCAUCUCUACUAAAUAUAAAACAUUAGCCAGGCAUGGUGGUGGGCACCUGUAAUCUCAGCUACUCGGGAGGCUGCAACAGGAGAAUCACUUGAACCUGGGAGGCAGAGGUUGCAGUGAGCCGAGAUGAUGCUACUGCACUCCAGCCUGGGCGACAAAGCGAGACUGUCUCAAAAAAGAACAUGGAGAAAGACCAGCACAUUAUAUUUACACAAACUAGGCCACCUAGCAAUCACCAACUCUGAAGUCCUACAAAGCCCAGACAAAUACAAUAACUAAUGGGGUGUGGGGGAAAGCAUUUAGGGGAAACAGGAACACAGGAUCAGGCACACACUACCCAAGUGCAUUUUAUUGCAUUUGAGAGACCACGUUUUCUUAUCUUCUUUGUAUCUCUGACAUUAUCUUCUUAGUGCCUGAUUAAUAGUUGUUGUUUUAUCUCUAAGUAAUUCUAAGUAACUAAGUUUACUUAGUAGUUGCCCAAUAAAUAGGCACCUACUAAAUAGGGAGUUAUUUAGUUACUUGUAAAAUCCUUAAUUUUGGAGAUCUUUCAAAAACAUUAAUACACCAAACCAGAUGACUUUUUAAGGCCCUUCAGUUAACUUUGGGUCUGCGGUUAGUAACUGAAAAUUAGAAUGGUAGAAGGCUUUGAAGUCCAUGUCAAGAAUCUAGACUGAUGUUUGUUUUAGAAAAUAUGGAAACCUUUCAUUUAUAUGGAGUUUUCAUAUAAAUUAUAUGGAGUAAUUCAUUAAGAAAUAGCUAUUGAACCAAGCACUGAUCAAAUUCCUAGAUAUUUGGCAGUGCAGAAUGUCCCUGUGCUUACAACAGAGUUUACAGUCUAAUAGGUAAUUGUCAAGUGAGAGGAAUGAAAUAAUCCACCUCUUGACAACAGAGAGAACCAUGAGGCUAGCCGUUUUUGCCUUUGCUUCUUUUUAAGUUUAAAACAAUAAAACUACAAAAAGUAUAUUGCUGCCAUUGACAAGGACCCAAUCUGCAUUUUGUGGUGUUUGUUCUUCUAUUGCAACUUCACUGCAGUAAUUUUUUGGAUGAGACUGAUCAUAAUGUGUGAUGUUUGUGCUCACAGUUUAUCACUGAUUACUAAAAUGCAUUUACUUUCUGCAUGUGGAUAAUACUGGUAUGAUAUUACCUUCCUUAGAGUUGGGGAGAUUUCUUUUUUUCUCUUUUUUUUUUUUAAUUAUGCUUUAAGUUCUAGGGUACAUGUGCACAACGUGCAGGUUUGUUACAUAUGUAUACAUGUGCCAUGUUGGUGUGCUGCACCCGUUAACUUGUCAUUUACAUUAGGUAUAUCUCCUAAUGCUAUCCCUCCCCCCUCCUCCCACCCCACGACAGGCCCCAGUGUGUGAUGUUCCCCACCCUGUGUCCAAGUGUUCUCAUUGUUCAAUUCCCACCUAUGAGUGAGAACAUGAGGUGUUUGGUUUUCCGUCCUUGUGAUAGUUUGCUCAGAAUGAUGGUUUCCACCUUCAUCCAUGUCCCUACAAAGGACAUGAACUCAUCCUUUUUUAUGGCUGCAUAGUAUUCCAUGGUGUAUAUGUGCCACAUUUUCUUAAUCCAGUCUAUCAUUGUGGACAUUUGGAUUGGUUCCAAGUCUUUGCUAUUGUGAACAGUGUCGCAAUAAACAUAACGUGUGCAUGUGUCUUUAUAGCAGCAUGAUUUAUAAUCCUUUGGGUAUAUACCCAGUAAUGGGAUUGCUGAGUCAAAUGGUAUUUCUAGUUCUGGAUCCUUGAGGAAUUGCCACACUGUCUUCCACAAUGGUUGAACUAGUUUACAGUCCCACCAACAGUGCAAAAGUGUUCCUAUUUCUCCACAUCCUCUCCAGCACCUGUUGUUUCCUGACUUUUCAAUGAUCGCCAUUCUAACUGGUGUGAGAUGGUAUCUCAUUGUGGUUUUGAUUUGCAUUUCUCUGAUGGCCAGUGAUGGUGAGCAUUUUUUCAUGUGUCUGUUGGCUUCAUAAAUGUCUUCUUUUGAGAAGUGUCUGUUCGGCCGGGCGUGGUGGCUCACACCUGCAAUCCCAGCACUUUGGGAGGCCGAGGCGGGCGGAUCACAAGGUCAGGAGAUCAAGACCAUCCUGGCUAACACGGUGAAACCCUGUCUCUACUAAAAACACAAAAUAUUAGCCGGGUGUGGUGGCAAGCGCCUGUAGUCCCAGCUACUCAGGAGGCUAAGGCAGGAGAAUGGCGUGAACCCGGGAGGCAGAGCUUGCAGUGAGCUGACAUCACACCACCGCACUCCAGCCUGGGUGACAGAGGAAGACUCUGUCUCAAAAAAAAAAAGAGAAGUAUCUAUUCAUAUCCUUUGCCCACUUUUUGCUGGGGUUGUUUGAUUUUUUCUUGUAAAUUUGUUUAAGUUCUUUGUAAAUUCUGGAUAUUAGCCCUUUGUCGGAUGGGUAGAUUGUAAAAAUUUUCUCCCAUUCUAUAGGUUGCCUAUUCACUCUGAUGGUAGUUUCUUUUUUUUUUUUUUUUUUUUUUGAGACAGAGUCUGGCUCUGUCGUCCAGGCUGGAGUGCAGUGGCGCAAUCUCUGCUCACUGCAAGCUCUGCCUCCCAGGUUCACGCCAUUCUCUUGCCUCAGCCUCCCGAGUAGCUGGGACUACAGGCACCCGCCACCACGCCCAGCUAAUUUUUGUAUUUUUAGUAGAGACAGGGUUUCACCAUAUUAGCCAGGAUGGUCUCGAUCUGCUGACCUCAUGAUUCGCCCACCUCGGCCUCCCAAAGUGCUAGGAUUACAGGCAUGAGCCACUGUGCCCAGCCCUGAUGGUAGUUUCUUUUGCUGUGCAGAAGCUCUUUAGUUUAAUUAGAUCCCGUUUGUCUAUUUUGGCUUUUGUUGCCAUUGCUUUUGGUGUUUUAGUCAUGAUGUCCUUGCCCAUGCCCAUGCCCUGAAUGGUAUUGCCUAGGUUUUCUUCUAGGGUUUUUAUGGUUUUAGGUCUAACAUUUAAGUCUUUAAUCCAUCUUGAAUUAAUUUUUGUAUAAGGUGUAAGGAAGGGAUCCAGUUUCAGCUUUCUACAUAAGGCUAGCCAGUUUUCCCAGCACCAUUUAUUAAAUAGGAAAUCCUUUCAGAGUUAGGGAGAUUUCUUAGGGUAUUGUUACCCUCAAGAUUAUAAAUAAUAUGAAUUUGUAAUGUUUAAUAAUAGCUAACAUUUAUUCAGUACUUUAGUGUAUUAACUCAUUCAAUGCUCAAAGCAACUAGUGAGGCAAAUGCUAUUACUAUAUUCACUUUACAGGUGAGGAAACUGAGGAAUAGAAGUGUUAACUAACCUGCUCCAAGUCACACAAUAAAUAGAACUCAGAUUUGAACACAGGUUCCAGCAUCUUUAAUUGCUAUGUAAUAUUAUGCAUUCAUCGCAUAAUAUUUUGGGACCAUUGAAGGUCCUAAAAGUUACCAUUGUAUUUAGAAAAAAGAGUACUGUUGGCUGGGCCUGGUGGCUCAAGCCUGUAAUCCCAGCACUUUGGGAGGCCAAGGCGGGCAGAUCACCUGAGGUCGGGAGUUCGAGAUCAGCCUGACCAACACAGAGAAACGCCAUCUCUACUGAAAAUACAAAAAAUUAGCCAGGCAUGGUGGUGCGUUCUGUAAUUCCGGCUACUCAGGAGGCUGAGGCAGGAGAAUUGCUUGAACCCGGGAGGCGGAGGUUGUGAUGAGCCGAGAUUGCACUCCAGCCUGGGCAAAAAGAGCGAAACUCCGUCUCAAAAAAAAGAAAAGUGUACUGUUAUCAUGUUCAAUUCUCGUGAGAAUCCUCUAAAGCUGGCAAAUCAUGUGAUAACCUUUGUACCUUAUGGAUGAGAAGACAGCCUUAGAGAAGUUAUUCUGUUUUGUCCCUGGUCACCCAAGACCUUUAGUGGGAUGAUUCCUCAUUCUUUAUGUGAACUCAGUUUUUUUUAUCCAGGGAAAUGAAGCAGAAAGAAAUAUUAAUAUGAAACAAAUAAAAUAAUCUUAAAACCUCAGUCUUAGUAUUCAACCCUUGACUUUACAUACUGCUUCCCAAACCUGUUGAGAACUGCCUCUAUUGGAAAGGCUGAAUAGCACCAUCAGCAUAGGAAGGGACAAAACACAUUUUUAGAAAUUAAAAGGGCACAAGAUCUUCUAUAGUGUCUAUCUUAGGGGAAAAAGUACCGGCACAAUAUUAAUUGCUAACUAGAUGAAUCUUGCUCCAGUUACUCCAGAGUCAACUUUGACAUUUUCUUCUCUUUGCAUUGGUACUUUAUUCUUUGUUAAACAUAUAAUUCCCUCCUACAUAUUUAAAAAGGUUUUUAUUCCUCUAAUAUAAUGACUUCAGAAGUCAGUCAUUAUUAACUCAGGUUAAAAAAAUAAUUUCUGAUUGAUUUUUUUAAUACAGAAUUUUGAACAAAAAGCAUUUCUAAAUCCAAAGAUUUUUUUUUUUUUUUUGAGGUGGGGUCUUGCUUUGUCACCCAGCCUGGAGUGCAGUGGCCUGAUGACAGCUUAUUGCAGCCUUGGCUUCCCAGGCUCAAAUGAUCCUCACACCUCAGCCUUCCCAAGGAGCUGGGACUACAUGUGCGCACCUCCACACCCAGCUAAUUUUUUAUUGUUAUUUUUUGUACAGGUGGGGUCUUGCUAUAUUGCCCAGGCUGGUCUCAAACUCCUAGGCUCAAGUUAUUCUCCCACCUCAGCCUCCCAAAGUGCUGGGAUUAUAGGCAUAAGCCACCACAUCUGGCCUUAAAUCCAAGAUUUUUAAGUAAUUUAUUGAAAGGAAUAUGUUCAUACUGCCUCCCAGUUUUCGGAUAAAAGAAACCCAUGCCCUCAGACAAUUUACUCUGAAGUCAGUUAAACUUUAGUAGUCUUUAGAGUGAAAAUAAUAUGUUCAUAUGAUACUGAAAUAUUUUACAUAAAAAGGAAUAUUGUCACCUACAAAUUGUAUACAUUUUUAUAAAGCUAGCUACUGCUAGAUUAAAAUGUGGUAUUAAUGAUAAUGUCACAAUUUAUAAUAUGUUGCCAUUAUAUAUUCUAUACUAUCUGAUAUAGUAAAUGGUAGCCAUUAGCCACUUGUCACAUGUGGCUAUUUAAAUUUAAAUUGUAAUUAACUGAAAGCACUUAAAAUUGUAAAAAUUACUCAGUUGUAUUAGCCAUAUUACAAAUACUCAAUAGCAACAGGUGGCUAGUGGCUACUGUAAUGAAUGGGGUAGAGCAUUUUCAUCAUCAUUGAUAGUUCUGGCUGGGCGUCGUGGCUUACACGUGUAAUCCUGGCACUUUGGGAGAUCGAGGUGGGUAGAUUGCCAAAGUCCAGGAAUUCAGAACCAGCCUGGGCAACAUGGCAAAGCCUCGUCUCUGCAAAAAGUACAAAAAUUAUCUGGGAGUGGUGGUGCGUGCUGGUGGUCCCAGCUACUCAGGAGGCUGAGGUGGGAGGAUCAUCUGAUCCUGAGGAGGUCUAGGCUGUAGUGAGCCGUGAUCACACCACUGCACUCCAGCCUGAGUGAGAGACCCUGUCUCAAAACAAAAACAAAAACAGAUAGUUCUGUUAGACCAGCACUGCCUAAGUAUUUGAUUGUCUAGAAUAUAAUUGUAAGAUUAGGAUCCAGGGUAUAGUAUAAGUGGGCUCAGUUUCUCCUCACAUUACUGUAAAAUAGUACAUUCAGCAGGGGUUUAAUAAGCAUCCAGUUUGUCAGCCAGAAAGUAACUUUACUGUGUUGUUCUUUUAUAGUAAUGGAAUAGAGUAGUCUCAAUUUUUUAAAAAUUAUUAUGGUAAUAUCUUUACUUUUUGGUAAUAAUUUUCUGUUUGAUCCGCCACUAAAAAGGUACAUAUAUCUUAGUAACAAGUAAAAAUAGAUUUGAUUGCUUUUAAUAUGUAUGCUUAAUAAUAUUUGUUCUUUCUUGGUUAUUUUCCUUACCUGGUACAGGUAGAAGAGUCAGCAAUGAUGGGAGUAAGUGGCUAUGUGGAGUAUCUCCGAGAGCAGGAAGUAUCUGAGCGGUGGUUCCGGUACAACCCUCGUCUCACCUGCAUCUAUUGCGCCAAAUCUUUCAACCAGAAGGGAAGCCUGGACCGCCACAUGCGCCUACACAUGGGGAUCACACCAUUCGUCUGCCGCAUGUGUGGCAAGAAGUAUACCCGGAAAGAUCAGCUGGAGUAUCAUAUCCGCAAGCACACAGGCAACAAGCCCUUUCACUGUCAUGUCUGUGGCAAAAGUUUCCCCUUCCAGGCCAUCUUGAAUCAGCACUUUCGCAAAAACCACCCUGGCUGUAUACCCCUGGAGGGGCCUCACAGCAUCUCCCCUGAAACAACUGUCACAUCUCGAGGACAAGCUGAGGAAGAGUCACCUUCACAGGAAGAGACAGUUGCUCCUGGGGAAGCUGUCCAGGGCUCUGUGUCCACCACUGGGCCAGACUGAAACAUCCAGGGGGAGGGGGCUGACCCUCUUCCCCUAUGAGCCAUAAGCAGCCAGCAUCAGAGCCAUGGGCUGAUACUUAGAUUCACAAAAUGCCACAUCACUAGGCCAGAAGAUGCUCCCAAGAUGUUGCCAAACUGGAGGAUCAGCAACUUACACAAAAGCACUAAAGGCUCCUCCCUUCUUAUUGCCCGCCUCACACUUUGGAAAAUAAUCAAGCAAAUCAACUUUCUAAUUCAGGGAUCAACAGCCUUGGUUUGUUAACUUUAUAAGAAAAAAGGUUUUUUAACAAAACGAUGAUGAUAAAUGGUCAUUUAUCUAUCAGUCAUGUUUGAACACUGUACUUUGGUCCAUAUCAUCUUGGUGGCUAUAAUUGCCCGGAUCUAAAAAAUGCAGCAGGAGCCUCAACCAUCCGAAGCAGCCAACCGCAAGAGAGGAGGUAGUCAUGAUGGUGAUGAGGAGGAGAAAUUUCUCCUCUUCCUUCCCUGGCAUAACAUGCAUUUUUGUGUUUCAAGAAAAAAAUGAAUACUGGUGGUUCUUAUUUUGAAAGGUUAGGCUUUAUCUUUCCCCUGACUAGGCAUCUAAUACUUUGCCUGGUUAUUUCAUAUAAUCAGCCAUCUUGAAGCAGUAUUCUAGUGGACAACAUCACCUGAAGCACUUGGCAACUGGGAGUGAAAUGAGCAGCAAAGUGUAUGCAAUAGGUACUGCUACAUUUGGGGGGCUUGAGUGUUGUGUUGAGGAAGAGGAGAGCAGGGAGGGAAGUGUUUUUAUGUUUUGCAAAUAUCAAACAGCACAGAGCCGUUCUGCAACUUCCUGACUGGUAUUUGUAAACCAUAGUGCUACACAUCCUUGGGUAAUGGCUCUAGUUCAGGUGAAUUAAUGUGUUAGGCUGACUACCAAAGUUUCAUCUAGUCUCUUUGGCUCCUAUUUUCACGUUCAGCAAUAUUGUAAUCAAAAAUGUCACUUUCCAGUGAAAUGAGCCUGGAUUGUAUUUUUAAAUCCACAGGUCUCCAUAUUUGAUAACUUUUAUAUGAAGUUUUAAACAUGUUUUUUCUGCAGUAUUGUGGUUGAAGAAAUUCAACACUAUGGUUCUUACUGCAACCACAAUUUCAUUUCCUUAUACAUAUGUAAUAGUUUAUAUUUUCAGGCAUAUAGAAGGACCUCACUUAAAACUAUGUCUCGGGUCUGCAAACCUAGUAAUUCAUAAACCAACCAUCAGCAAACCAUAGCUGGUGACUCCAAGAGCUUUGCUUUUUAAUAAUAUACUACAGGGCACUUAUCAGAAAACAUCAUGCAGAAUCAUGUUGCAAUAAAUGAUCAAAGGAUCAAUUUUGGUCAGGUUUGGUUACUUAGUCAUUCCUAAGAUUUUUAAAACUUCAAGGGACCCUUUUAGUAAUUCUGGGUAUUUCUAAGAUUCUUAAUCCAGCACUGAGAGAAAGAACUUAGCAAACAUGUAGAGCUUUGGAUACCCCGUCUUUCAUGAAGUGAGAGAAGGAGGAAUAUUAAGGGAUGCCGGCAAAUAGAUGCUUAUAACUUACAGUGCAAGUUGAAAAAUCUCUAGCUUCUGUUGACGGAGCACUAGUUGUUGGGGUUCUUUUAAGUAUGUAAUGGUUUAAGAAAUUGUUUCAGUGCAGAGGCAUAGAUGACUGUAAAAGAGAUUUGGCAGAGGGACAGGUUGUACCUGCACUGGUGAACCAUCUGUGAGAAUGUUAGUCAUGUGCUCCUUUCCUGAGAUUGCUUUGUGGUAUGUGAAAAGGUGGGUAGAAAAGAAAGAAAUCUCUUUGAGAUAAGAAAUUAGAAUGCAAAGGGUAGAUCUUAAGCAAUCUGAGAAUUGUACAUGUACAUAAAGCUGCACCCUCUCACAAGAGAAAGGUUAUUUUAUCUUCUGAAAAAGCAUAGAAAUGCAUCUUUUAUGGGAAGAUAAUGAUGCUACCAUUUAAUAAGAGCCUACCCUUAAAGGCAGCAUUGAAACUGUAUUUUGUCUUUAGAAGACAUAGACUGGUGCAUCCUCCGCUUUAGUUAGACAACAGCAUGAUAAGGAAAAAACUGUCUUCUAAAGCCAUCUUUAGGGACUGGCUGUGCUCUGUGGCAUAGAAAAGGUAAAGUUGAAUUAGCCAAAAAUCCUUAGGGAAACAACUGGUAAUAAGGUUUUCAGUGGACAGAUUUUGUCAUUACUAAAUAGGCAGUGAGGUGAGAAGUACAGAUUAUGCUGCUUUGGAUGGAGCCUUUAAGCCUACCAAAAAACUUUUAAGUCCAUCCUACUUUUGAGAAAUAGUAUGCUAGAAAGUUCUGUUUUUCUUUUUCUUCUUUUUUAUAUUUUUUAGAGACUGUGUCUUCCUCUUGUCACCCAAACCAGAGUGCAGUGGUGCAAUCAUAGCUCACUGUAAUCUUGAACUCCUAGGCUCAAGUGAUUGACCUGCCUCAGCCUCCAGGUAGCUAGGACUAUAGGCAUGCACCACCAUGUCUAGCUAAUUUUUAAAUUUUUUUGUAGAGACGGUGUCUCUACAAAAUUUGCCUAGGUUGGUCUUGAACUCCUGGCCUCAAGUAAUCCUACCACCUUGACCUCCCGAAGUGCUAGGAUUACAGGCAUGAGCCAGUGAACUUGGCCUGGAGAAAGAAUUCUUUGUUGCUUUGUUAGUUUCUUAGAUUAUAUGUGAGAAAAUGGAGCUUUUUAAACUAUUACCAAAUUUUAAAGGUGAAGUGCAGUAAUUUCUGUAAAGAGAAACUUUGCAGCAUUUGUCAAUUCUCCUUCCAGGGUUAGCAACAAACAAAUGAGGUAGGGACUAUCUCAUUCAUGUGGAAAUGCUAUGAAUGUUUGGUGGGUUUCCCCUCCCUUUUCUUUUCAUUCACUUUAAAUAGCCUUUUCCUAUAUUGAUACUGUGAAUAGGGUGCUUCCUGGUCAUCUAGGACCACUUUAGCACAAUCAUGUUUGCUGGUUCUCUCAAUUGGCCUAGCCAGAGCCACAAAAUUCAUGAAAAUUUAAGGCAGGCUAGCUUUUAAACAAAUUAAAACUUCUGAAAACAAUUUCAGCUUUUUCGUUAAAAGAGAUGUUGUUAUUCUAAAUAACUGUCCAAGACUCUUACCCACAUACACUGUGACAUUGUCCUAGUUCUUAGCUAACAACACAUUGGUCAUAGGAGUUACUGAUGUUCUAUCUACAUUAAUGAACAGCUAUUGGUGUAUGCACAGAGGAUACCUCUUAAGGAUGUACUAAAUGGACUUUGUUUGGUUGAUGCUGAAAAUUAAUUACCAAAUCUUAACUUGCACGUGUUACCUUGUGAAGGGAACUGCAUUAGCAAUGAGAGCUACAUCAUCAUGAAGUACUUUAAUGCCAUGAAAUUGCAAACACUGGGACUGUUUUCAUUUAUUGAGUGGCACUUAGUAGCAAAGGAGCUAUCCAGUAUUCUCAGCAAAGAAGAGAGACGGAAGUAUAUUAAUCUAUUUUCAUACUAAGAUGUUCCUUUAUUCUGUCUGAACUCUAAUACCAGUAUAAAAUAUAGCAUUGGCAUGAACAGUUAAUGCUGUACUUAGGCAGAAAGGCUCCUUCUAAUGACUUGUUCUCUCUUUACUCAGAACCGUAUUUACCUCUGAACCAAGUUGAAUUUUAUUUUAUCCAAGUUGCAAACUACCCCAUGCCAUUUUUAUUAUAAUAGAGGGUUAAAUCUAAUCUCAAAUACAUAAAGGUAAAUUAGUUCAUAGAGGAUAAAGUUUGGGAAUGAAGAGAGCAGUUAAGGAAAAUUUUAUUUUUUGUCAUUUUUUAAAUGUUUCCAGUUCCCUCUACAUCAGUGAAACAGGGUUUUCCAAAGAUGGUUUGAAGAUAGAAAAAACUUUUUCCCCCCGACUUCAUAGUUGACAUCUGGUAUUGGUUGGAAUUGGUCUGGUGGCAGAGUGAAGUAGGGAACUUCAUUUUUUUCUUUUUUUUCUUAAAGGCAGGGUCUCACUAUGUUGCCCAGGCUGGUCUCAAACUCCUGGGCUCAAGUGGUCCUCCUUCCUCAGCCUCCUGAGGAGCUGGGACUACAGGCGUGUGACCACACCUGGCUGUAAAUGUCAUUCUUAAUAGCUGAAUAAUCUUUGGUCAAGAAGUAACUUUUCCAGAGUUUUAGCUGUUACUUGACAUUAAUUGGGUUUCUUUUAACUGGUGAAAACUGUAUUUAUUUUGUUUGACCAGACUGUCUAACUUAAAUGAAAGCAAUGGAUAAUGGAAAGGAAACUGAACAAAGACAAAAGUCUUCUUCAUCAUAGUGAAAGGCAUUUAAUCAGGAAGAGUUGGAAUCCUGGAAGUUUUUCUUUUUUUCAGGUACAAGAGGCAUGAUUUUUUUCUCUUCCUAAAAUGUCCUUCCCCUUAUCUGUGUACUUAUUAGUUCAAGGAAUAACAAAUGAGUCUUAAUUGAACUUAGUCUUUGGAAAUUGAGCUCUUUAUUUAGGUUAUAUGUGAAAGAGUUUAAAAUAUUGAAAUACUUUGGUUGCUAAGCAGAUUUAGAAAAGCAACAAGCAAUUGUCGGGCAAAUCCCUAGGUUUGAGAAGAUGUCCUCAGCAAAAUAUACCCUUAGGACUUACGGAAUUAGAUCAGGGUUCAGCAAACAGUAGUUUCCAGGCCAAAUGCUGAGGCUACUUGCUUGUGUAAAGAAAAUUAUAAUGGAAUAGGGCCACACUUACUUGUUUAGGUAUUGUUUAUGCCUUCUUUCUACUACAAUGGCAAAGUUGAGUACUUGUGACAAAGAUCACGUGGCUACAAAGCUUGAAAAUAUUUACUGUCUGGUACUUGUUAGAAAAAAUUUGCCAACUCCAAGAAAGAAUUACCUCCUAAAGUUGUUACUCAUGACAUUUUGCCUUUAUAAUAGUUUGGUUGAAGUUUUAAAUUCAUGUUGUCACAUAUACAUGUUUUCUUGAAAGAGUUUGCCAACUUUUUCUAGAUCCUCUUAUCAUAACUCUUUUUGUGCUCCUUCAUGAUUUUUUUGUGCUCCUUCAUGAUUCCCAUUACUUUAAAAGCAUUUAGAAUUGGCCUGUUGUUUGUCCUUGUCUUAAUGGUGCCGGUAUUUUAAAGUUUAGUUGUAAGUAAGUUUUGCCAUUCCUCUGAGUUAACUUGAACUGGUUUGCAUAAUGGUGACAAGAAUGAAUUUUUUCCCAAGUGGAUUAAAAACUAAUUUCAUUAUGAAGAAGUAUUUUGAUUCAUAUCCAAAGUACUGUUUUUCUGGAUUAGAACCCCUACCUUUUCCCUUUGCAAUGUAUCUUAAUUUUAACUUCUUUAAACUUACUCUGUUCCAUGUAGAGCAGUAAAAAGCCAAGUUUUUCUUCCUUUUUUCCUGGAUGUUUUGAAACAUAAUGAAACAUCUGAGGAUUUCAAAUUCUUUUUAGACCUAUCUUCCCAUUUCUGUUAUUGUCUAUAAUUCUUCUAAAUACAUAUUGGACCAUUAACAUGUUUGCUUUGUGAAUGUUCAUUCUUAGUGUUCAGAUAGCCUACUUAUACUCGAUGUGGGAAAAAUGGGAAAUGUUAGGGGGUUCAUAAACAGAAAUCCUUGCAGGAAGCCGGGUGUGACAGCAGACACCUAUAAUCCCAGCUACUUGGGAGACUGAGCUGAGAGGCCCACUUGAGGCCAGGAAUUUAAGGACCAGCCUGGGCAACAUAGACCUUAUCUCUAAAACAAAAAAAAAUCCUUGCAAGAAGAGAGAAUAAUUGCUUCCCAUUUGGAAAUGAUAUAGGGACUUUUGAAUUAGAUCUAUCUUGACAAAGUUUUCUAGGCCAUGCUGAUACAGUAUAGGGAGUUUGAAUCUGUUGUGAGCGCUGUCAACAUAGACAAAGUUCAAGUGAGUAACUAGCUUUCUAUAAUAGGGACUCUCUUCACUAGGUAUUUUAAAGUUGCUGCUUUCUAAUUGGAUAUUAGGAAGUUUUAUAUGAUAUACCCUCUGAGUAAUAGAUAAUCCUCAUCUAUAAAGUUCCAGAAUAUUUGCCUAGGUUAGAUCUCCCCUGGCUUAGAGCAGUUAUACCUAUAGUAACAGUAGGUUUUUGAGAUUUUGGAGUAUUACUUUUCUGAUUAACCUAGGAUUCUGAUUAACCUGGAAGGUGGGACUUGUGAAAGAAAUUGGAUUUUGUUAGCCCAGUGAAUCAUCUGCAUCCCACUCUAUUUGAGGUCUUGGUAAUAGAUGUCAAUUUAAAUAUGCAUCUAUUGAAAGCAAUGGAGUUUUCCAAGCAUUAUGACUUCCUUGAUAAUUUUCAGUCUUAUCUUUUUUCGUAUUUUCUAGUCUCUUUCCCUGUCUUUAGUCUUCUUCCUCUUAAAUGGUGCUUUUCCCAGGGCCAGUCUUUCUACUUUCUAAGCAAGCAGGCUUUUUUGUUCAGGAUAAGCCAGAGUUAGAUAUUAUGAAUACUUUGAAACAUCUGAAUAUGUUACAUUCCAAAGUAUGUAAUUAUUGAUAGUAGUAUCAAAACCUGGAAGAUAUUGGUGCAGAUUAUUCAGUUUUGCUGUGUAGGCAGGCUGUCUUUCUCCUCAACUGUGACACAGCAGUGACUUGAGAAGGCAAAUAUUACUUGAAACCCCCAUUAUCUUUAUAGAGGGUACGUAUAUAAAUUUUCUUACCUGACAUUUUUACCAUUAUCAAUAUAUCAGUAGCUCACAUCUUAACAUAGAAGAAGCCCAUUAGCUCAAAUACUGGAAACUUCAAACAAGGAAAUAAAUUACAAAAGCAAAGCAGUUAAUGAAAAAAACUUGUCUAUUGCCUGCGUCUUUCAUGUCUACUCAAUAGGUCCUGUUGAGGAGGCUAGAAUACACCAUCCGGUUAAGAAAGGGGUUGUUUUGUUUUGUUUAAGACAGAGUCUUGGUCUGUCUUCCAGGCUGGAGUGCAGUGGCUCAAUCUUGGCUCACUGCAAUCUCCACCUCCUUGGUUCAAGCAAUUCUUGUGCCUCAGCCUCCCAAAUAGCUGAGAUUACAGGCGUGUGCCACCAUGCCCAGCUAAUUUUUGUAUUUUUAGUAGAGAUGGGGUUUCACCAUGUUGGCCAGGCUGGUCGUGAACUCCUGGCCUCAAUUGAUCCUCCUGCUUCGGCCUCCCAAAGUGCUGGACUUAGAGGCAUGAACCACUGCACCCAGCCCCAUUUAAGAGAGUUUUAUAUUCAGCAUCUCAUAUGGCCUACACCAUGAUUUUAAUAUACUGUGAAUCUUAGGAUUUCAGUUAAUCCAUAAUGCCAGGAGUUAAGGUAUUUCAUGGGAACAUGUUUCCUCUUCUAUGAAAUCACCUGUCUGCAGUGAUAGGUAAUGUAUAAGAGAAUGUUUCAUUAAGUAAAUAUUAAGUACUUUUUGAUACCAGACAACAUGCUUGGGAUUUGUAUAAUAAAACUGGUUUUAGACAUAGUUUAGACAUGAUGUGUCUUCCUAUACUUGAGAGUCCUAAGCCCACUUGGUUGGCGUCUGGGAUGUAUUGCUUUUGAAAAGCCUGCACUUUUUACUGUAGAGAUAAAAGAUCAAAAAGGGGACAGAAUUAGCUUUAUUAAGUGCUUUAUCGUCAUAACUGUGGUUAAGACAAUAAUACUAUGAGGUAAUAACAGUAAUGUUAAAAAUAACUAACUUUUUUUGAAUGCUUACUAUGUGCCAGGCACAGUUCUAUGUGCUUCACAUUGAUUAACUCAUCUAAUCCUUAUGACAAUCCCAUGAGGGUAGAUAACAUCCUCAUUUUAGAUGGGAAGAAACAGACACAACUGACUCAGGCUAACACUAGAGUUGCCUCUAGUAGGUGUAAUUAUAUCAUAUUUUAUAGAUGAGGAAACUGAUGAACCCAAGGUUACAUAACUGGUAAAUUACAGAGCCAAUAUUUACCAAUCUUGAUUCCAAAGCCCAGACUAUCUGCAUGAUGUCAUAUUGACUCCAUUUACUUAUCAAGAGUUGAAGUUGACUGGAAUAUACAGUAGCCAGGAACAGUACUGCUUUUUGUGAAUGUGUAAUUCAAGAGUAAGUGAUUAGAAGGUUCUUCAAAAGCUGAUGCAGUUGAUCUCUGAGCAGAGUUGAAUAGUGAAUAUUUUCAGUGGAUAUUGCCCACUGAUUCAAGGGAGUCACCCGUGUGGUUAGGUCUAAUAGUGAGUGAGGUACUAUCAAGGCAAAAAUUGAAAGAGUUCCAGUUACCUAUUGCUGUGUAACAAACUUAAUUAAAAUUAAGUAAUUUUAAUUACUUAAAAUCAACCAUUUCCUAUAUCAUGGUUUUGUGAAUCAGAAAAUCCAGGAAGGGCUUGUCUGGGCAAUUCUCCUCCCUGUGACAACGACUCAGGUCACCUGGUGGUAUUCAGCAGGUGGUUAGACAAGUCUGGAAGGAGUGUCCAAGAUGAUCGAUCUUACAUACCUGACACUUUGGUGGGGAGACUAGAAGGAUGGACUCAGCAGGUCUCCUCUUUCUCUCCAUGAAGUCUAAGGACUCUCCAUGUGUUCUCUUCAUCAAGGUAGUCAGAUUUACUACGAGGACAGCUAAGGCCUCUGAAAGGCUGGGCAGAAGAAUCUAGUCAACUUAAAGGCCAGGCCUAGAAUUAUCAUACAGCCACCACUGUACUCUUGGUCGAAGAACUUAAUGGUAAGAUGACAGCAAGAAUGAAGGGGGAAAAAAGAACUCAAUGGUCAGCCCAAAUUUAAGGAGAGAAGAAAUACCCUACCACUUUAUGGAAGGCAUGUCCAGGACUUGGGGCUAUUUUUAAUGUGUUAAUGUUUUUUUUGUUUUGUUUUGUUUUUUGUCUUGACUCUUUGGUGUUUAUUCAUCAGUUGUUUGUGCUGUAGAAACCAUUUAUUAUGUCUACCAUGGGUCACUAAAGGAGCUAGAAGGAGAAUGAGACAAAUAUCUGGAGCAUACUUCAUUUGCUGCCCUCUCCCUCCAAGUUUCAUUUAUCUUAUAGCAAAAUUUUCAUUUUGUACUGUGUUCCAAGUUGUGAACAUUUGCCUGGUUUUGCUCUGAAGCCACGGUAACUGCAUGCGGAGCUAGAAAUACUCUAGAGGGAGUAAAAAGCUUACAUUUUUUUUGUUUGUUUUUUGUUUUAGGACAGAGUUUCACUCUGUCACCCAGGCUGGAGUGCAGUGGUGCAAUCACAGCUCACUGCAGCCUCAACCUCCUGGACUCAAGCAAUCCUCCUACCUCAUCCUCCCAAGUAGCUGGGACUCCAGACGUGUGCCACUACACCUGGCUAAUUUUUGUGUAUUUUUAGAGACGGGAUCUCACCAUGUUGCCUGGGCUGGUCUUGAACUCCUGGACUCAAGAGAUCCACCUUCCUCGGCCUCCUGAAGUGCUGGGAUUACAGGCAUGAGCCAACGUGCCUGGCCCGGAAAGCUUACUAUUAAAUAAUUUGAUUUCUUGGAGAUAUCAGUUGUAUUUUAAGUUUACAAAUAGGUGAAUACUCUUGUGGUAUGGAAACAUUGCAUGGCUGCUGAAUCUCUUUCAACAGGAGUUUCUAUUGGGUGGCUACAUGGAUCAUAUUCUUGAGAUAGUGAAAAGUUUUACCUACUUAUCUUAAUCCCAUUCUACCUCUACACCUCCAGCAUGAUUUUGUGCUCGAAGAUGAAUCAAUUCCUUUCAUUCUUGUUACCUUUCAUACAGGAAAAUUCAUCGCCCAAUUUUAUAUGUUGUUAAUCUUUUAAAAUUGGCAGUUGUUACCAGCCUCUCUCAUUUAAAAUAACAGAUCAUUGAAGUUUUUUGAUUUUUGGUUAGAUGUGUCAGAUUUAGGAUGCCUUAUUUAAACUCGUGCUGUCUUACUAGACUGUUCCUGCUCUGAGAAGAAAUAUGGACAGAGAAUGAAUUUCAUUGUCCAUAUUGAUGAACCCCAAAUCAAUACACUUCUUAAGAAAGGUUUGAGAUUAUCCAGUCCAUGUGCAAUGAAUCCUUGGAGCAUUAGCUGUGUGGCCUUCCUACUGAUAAUCUGCAGUUAUCACAGUAAAGAGAUCUCUGUUCCUAGGUCAGGCCUUAGCAAUUACAAAUACAGGAAAUAAAGGGGUACUCAAUGCUGAAGACUUAAUUUUGGGUACCUACAAAGUCCUGGGAAGGGAAAAAGAAGACCUUGGCAUUUGUAUUUGCAUAACCAGAGAUGGAAUGUUUGAGGCUUUUAGGCAUAAAGAUUAAUUAGAUUUUAUCAUAUAAAGAUUAGGGCAAAUUAUUUUUUUUUCCAGUUCAUUCUUAACAUGUUAAGGGACAAAUUUUAAUGAAUAAAAAUUUAAAGGCCUUAAAACUUUCUUUUGGAUUCACAUUUCCACUCUGGUAUAAUCCACUCUGGUGUAGUCUGCCCUUUAUGACAGAGAAAGCCUUUGAAAAUAUUGUCCCAGGGAAUGAAAAAUCUUAAUGAUGAUCUAUGGAAAUGUCUCUCAUUCUCUAUUACAGCCCUUUGGGCCCUCCUAUAGAUUCUCUGUGAAUUUAAGUUUGAAAUCAUUUGGUGUUUGCAUGAAAAAUAAUUCUUACUAUUCAUUUAAAUAAUUCUUAAAUGUGGUCUUAAAUUGCAAGAGAGAACAAAGCCAGAAAAAGGGGAACCUUGUAGAUUGACCAAAUAUUUAUUCUUUAUUUUCAGCAUCACAAAUCUAAACCAUUUCAAGCUAAUACAACAACCUGAGUGAGUAGAAAUUCCUUAAGGUUUAGAUUUCUGCUUUUAGUCACAUCUUGAAGCAGAUGUUUAUGACAUAUUUGAAGAUGAUCCACUGAGUUUCCUAUAAAGUAAUAGAAUCCUAACUAUAGUGGUUCUUUAAGAACCACUGAAAAAACAGAAUUGCAGUGCAGGGAACAAAGCUUAAAAUGUGUUUCCUCUGGAAGCCAAGAUGCUAAAAAAGGGGUCACUAAUAGUGUGACUGAAGUCCGUCUCUAGAAUGGCUAUCUGUUAGAUAGCAGAAAUAUUUAGAAUGUAUAUGGCAUUUCUAAUAUUUUUACAAAAAUAAUUUUAAAUCAUGUAACUCGAAUUUUUUUUAAAAAGUCUGUUUUCUUUUUGGAAAACUGGCACAAUAAAAAUAACACUAAUAUAAUUCCAUUGUAUAUGCAUGUGCAUUGAACCCAGAGUGGGUAUACUAAAGAUAGUUCAUGCAAAUAACUUAUGGGAAGUUUGGCUAUUUUUUCAUGUAUGUUUAUAAAUAUAUUUAGUCAUCUACUGUGACCUUGGUAGCACAGAAGCAUUUUGUUAGCUGUAUCAUUAAUUCUAAAAAUCAAAUUCUUGGCAUAGUAGGCUAUGAGAGCUUUUUGUUACUUGGUAUUUUGGCUAAGAAAAUUAUUUCUUGCACUUUCUAUUUGUAAAGAUGUUAUAACACAAUGCACCCACUUAAUGCAGCUUUUCUUUAGAGAAAAAAGAUGUAGGUGUAAAAGUGAAAUGUAUGUUUUCAAACCUGGCAAAAGGAGGGACCUCAAAAAAAUAAAUUUGGCUUGCCAUCUACCUGAGUAGGGUUGGGGAUUAAUAUAAAACUUAGGUUGAAAGUGGCUGUUGGGAUAGGUAUACUGUUGCUGUGAAUUGCAAUAUUGCUGUGAGUUGCCAGCUAUGUAUGUGUAAGUUUAUGUGUGUAUGUGAGAAAAAGGUAUUUCGUGAAGGCAUAAAAGUCAGUGUAGAAUAUCCUACCUCCCACUAGAGACUGAGCAUAUUCAAGAUUGCUCUGUAGUCCCUUGGGCAGGAAGCUGGAUUCCUCAGCCACUGUCUACCCCAUUCUUCUCUAUACUCACUUCAGCUCCUCUACCUCUGAGCACUUGGCUGAAGAAAGAGUAUAGCUUUCUGUAGCAAGCAAAGGAAAGCCAGACCCAAAAUAGAGAGGCUGCAGUAUCUGAAAUUCUUAUCAUGUUCAGAUAUCAAUAUUUAAUUUUGUUGCCCAAAUCAAACAAUGUCAGAACACUUGAGUUUAGUGCUUUUUUUUCUCUCUCUGUCUCCUACAGACUUCUCCCGGUUUACUGCUUUUAUCCACUGGCUUCUGUUUGGCAGGAGUAGCCAGUGGAGGUCAAGUCUGUUUUUAAAGACUAAAACACCUAAUUCCUUUUAAUGAUGUGUAACAUUUGUUUGAAUCCCCAACUUCUUUUUUUUUGGGGGGCAGGGGUAGAGAUGGAGUCUCCCUAUGUUGCCCAGUCUCGUCUUAAACAUCUAGGUUUGGUUGGAUGCAGUGGCUCACACCUGUAAUCCCAGCACUUUGGGAAGCUGAGGUAGGCGGAUCACCUGAUGUCAGGAGUUCGAGACCAGCCUGGCCAACAUUGUGAAACCCCGUCUCUACUAAAAAUACAAAAAAUUAGCUGGGUGUGGUGGCGGCAUCUGUAAUCCCAGCUACUCGGGAGGCUGAGGCAGGAGAAUCGCUUGAACUCGGGAGGUGGAAAUUGCAGUGAGCCGAGAUCACACGGUUGCACUCCAGCCUGAGCAACAAGAGCGAGACUCCAUCUCAAAAAAAAAAAAAAAAAGUCUGGGCUCAAGCGAUCCUACCACCUCAGCCUCCCCAAAGUGAUAGGAUUACAGGUGCCAGUCACCACACCUGGCCCAUGAUGGAUUUUCAGAUGACCUCUUUUACUUCUAAUCUCUCCAAAGAGAGAUAUUCUUGUUUUUAAGGUCAAUAUUGUCAUAAUAGUCAUGAUGUCCUCACCUGAAUGUUGUAGGUGUCAGAAAGUUGUUUCAAUAGUAAUAUGCCACCAGGCAGACCACCUAAUCUUUAAAUCCAGUUGUAGCACUCAAUUUAUUUUCUGUUUGGGGCACUAGUGCACUGAGCCAAGUCAACUUGUCCACUUUUCUAAUAUUUCUUACAGCUAAGGAGGAACUGUUGGUCCUUUGAUAUCCUAGAAUGCUUUCUACUUGUGGAAAUGCUUUUUACCCUAAUACACUGAUUAUAUUGUCUAAAUGUCUAAACAGGGAUUCUCUGGUUAGAAGUGAAAUGAGAGAGUGACCCAUUUUCAGAUUUUUAGAGAUUGGCUCCCGUAUUUUAGGAACUAGCUGAUAAGUAUUUAGUUUCCUGGUGACUUUGGAUACGGCAAGUGGAGAUGCAGAGAAUGUGAAAUUCCAAAUAAUAAGACAAGCAUUACUCACAAAUAACAACUGAUACAGUAAUUUCUGCCCAAAUGCAGUAAGAAUCUUGUAGGGAGAUGAAGUGGUAAAAUUAAAUUAUAUGAAUCUUUUUACCACGACUAUUUUUUUUUUUCUACCUGUAGCAUAGUUCUCUGCCUAUAAGCCAUGCUAAUAUCCUAGACCCAGGAAUUAAUUCCUGCUUAGGAAAAUUUUUCCUUCUGGCUUAUCUUUUGUUUGUGCCCAGAGUUUUGUCCUAGGCCUGUCCCCUGAUCUUUUGCUAUAACACAUACUUAAGGUGCAGCCUUCUUACCUAAAUCAGUACUUUACUGUUGCUGUUGCUGCCUAUUACAGCCAGUUAUUUAUUUAAAAAGUAGUGAAAAAAUGCCUAGGUAGUUUGAUUGCAGCAUGUUAAAUCCAUAAAUCUGGACAGAAGCCAUGGAGUCUUACCUUUUCUCUCUCUAGCUUGGAUGAACACCGGCCUUAUGCUUUCUAUUACAGGACUAGUUGACCCAGUUCUUCAUAUUGGUUGCACAUUAGAAUUGCAUAGGACCCCCUCUAGACAUUUACAUUUUAUUGGUCUGUUGUGCAACCUGGGCUUUAGGUGAUUCUAAUGUGCAGCCAAGGUUGAGAAUCACUCCCUAUGUAAUCCCUAGUGGUCAUGGCAGGAUAACCUCAAUCCAGUCCUCUUUGACCUGAAAAUAUCUUUAUUGAUAUUCCAUGCAUGGCUCUCAAUUCAAAGUGUACAGUGGGUCAAGGCUUAGGUAGUAAAAUGGAUCAUCCAUUUGUCCUCAGAAUAAUUCUGGAGGGAGAUAUUGUCAUCCAUCCAGUUUCCUCUCUAUACCAAAUACAAAGUACACAUAAAUAAGCAAAACAAAUUUUCAAAGUUCCUUCUCUAGAAUCCUCUUUCUUUUGCAUAUGUAGUUUCAGUGGAGAUUUCUCAACUAGCUGAAAUGGAGCACUUGAAUAUAUUAAAAGAGCCCAAACUGCUUACAGCAAUUUCUAUUUGUAAAAUAAACAGGUGGCAUUGUUAAUGGAGAAAAGGAAGGAUCCUGCCUGUGGUGAUGGUAAUAUGUUUGAUUAUUUAUCUCUUAGCCUGUCUUCUAAGUGGGAUUUCAGUGUCAGUUAACUUUCACUUUUCUUGGAUUGUUUUUUUGUGAAUGAAAUGAACUAGUUAAGGCUUAAGUAUUUCUGAAUAAUAUAUGAAAUGUGAAAUGAGUCAUUUUAGGAUCUUUCUUCUGGGAUGUCAAAGACCUAACCAAGUAACUCCCAAAUGAGGUUCCAGAUUCAUUUUUCUCAUCCCAGGUAGUAAACGUGUUUUAAUGGGUUUGUUUCUUGCCCAUGGCAACCUCAACACAGAGGGGAGAACUGUUUUAUUACCCUAAAAUAGUGAGAACCACUGUUCAAACUAACUAGCUACCAAGUGACUUCUAACUCAUGAAGAAAAUUUGUAUUUAAGAGCAAGUUCAAAUGUAGCAGGCUCUCUUCUGAGAGUAUUCUGGAUACCACGGAAAGUUUCAUUUAUAUAUUGCUUACAAGUACGUGGUAAUUUGAACUUCAGUAGGUGAUAUGUGCAAGGAGAAAAAGUAGGUCAAGGAGAAAGUUGGUUAGUGCAGAGGACUGACUUAGCAUCAGUCUGUGAAAUUUCAUUAAAGUAGCACUAAGGCCUGGCUGUUUGCUUAGCAUGUAAAUGCUGCAGUGUCCAAGAAAAUGCCUCCUAUGCCUUAGAAAAUUUGCUGAAGGCUUCCUGUUACUGGUGGAGUAGAAAAGCAAUAGCCUUUGAGACUCCAAAGAGAGUAGCCCCCUUAGGGUUUUCAUACUGAAGAACCUUGUGGAGUACUGUGAAACAUUGUUGAACUUUAUGCAAAUUAUACUGCACUGGAUUUUAAGAUUUUAUGGGGAGAGAGUAGAGCAGAGUGGGGAAGUAAUGAUAAAAGAUAAAUACGUAAACUUGUACUAUAUUUUAAGCAAGGAAUGAAACAAAUUCCCUAACAGGAAUUCCCUGUCAGCACUGUGAAGUUUGGUCAAGUUCUGCCUAAUGGGUUGGCUUGCUGAUUCCUCUUAAACCUCUAGGAAAUCCUUUCUAAGACAGCAAAACAAACGUUAGUUUGAGUACUACUAUUUCACCACCCUGCUCCAUCCCCCUACUCUCAACGAAAGAAAAGCAUUCCCAAACUAUAGGCAAAAGAAAUGUGUUCUCAGUCCAUUAAUUUUUCAUCUGCUAUGAUCUCUGUUCACAGUUUUAGCACAUUGCAUUAUUUUGUAAUCUGAUAGCAGAACAUCAGGAACUAAUGGCUUCCUUCCCUUUAAGAAAUCUUAAAGUUAGAACUUUUUUUUUUUUUUUUUUUUUUGAGACAGGGUCUUGAUCUGUCACCCAGGCUGGAGUACAGUGGUGCAAUUAUAGCUCACUGCAGCCUCCACCUCCUGGACUCUAUCCUCCUGCCUCAGCCUCCCAAGUAGCUGGAACUACAGGCAUGUGCCACCACGCCCAGCUAAAUUUUCUAUUUUCUUUUAGAGACAGAGUCUCACUAUGUUGCCCAGGCUGGUCUCAAACUCCUGGGCUCAAGCGAUCCUCCCACCUAGGACUCCUAAAGUUACAGGUGUGAGCCACUGUGCUUGGCCUAGAACUCUGUUUUUGGCAUUUCUUUCUAAAUGAGUACAUUGGAAGAACAUUUAGGUUUCCAGGCUCCUCAUAAUUUCUGAAUGGGACCCGCUCUGCUCUGCCUCUGAAAGGAGGAGAAAAGGCUGAGGGUUCAAAGACAGAAAAGUCAAUGUAGCAGAAAUUUGAUUUCCUUCAGAUGGACAUAGUCUGAAAGAAAUCUAUCCAGCUGUUCUCUAUGGUGCUUAUAUGAUGGGUGACAGCUGUCCCCAUCUACCUGUCCCUGGCACUGUGCCUUCACACUGGUCACUGUGAAAAGCAGAUCACACUGGACUCAGAGGCCAGAAUCCAGGACAAGAUCCCCCUUCUCAUCUUGAGCCCAUCACAUCUUUGUAUAGCUGUUAAUGUAGCAUUUACUUCUCUAUGGGAAACUCUUGGGUUUUUAACCCAAGAAGAAAUUGUAAAGCAUUUAAACUAGUCAGAAAAUAAGAUUCUGAUGGUAGCGAUCAAAUAAAGGAAAAUUUCACUUCCUCUCAGUUGAUAUUGAUUGAUAGCAAGGAUCAACUAUGCCCACCUCUUCCUAAGUUUCUAAAGGCUACCAUAAUAUUUGUAAACAACAAAUUUAUCUAAUAUUUUUUACAACUUGCUAAUCAAGGAGGAUUCAUAUUAAAACAGACAAUCAGUUUCUAAAAUGUUAUCCCUGAAAGGGAAUGGAAUAGAGUAUUUUUAGCUGUAAGAACCUACCAGUCUGUUUUUUCCCUUUGAAAAAAACUAAUGUUUGAGAUUUGUGUCUUUUCAUCUGAAGCAGUUACUCCAUUAAUAGUAAAGAUGCCUCGGGAAAGUCAGUGAACCAGAAUAGUGCUCUUGCACCACUGAGGGUGCUAGACUGGCUUUGUGCAUCUUAUUUCCUAAGAAUAUCAGUUUUUAUUAUGACCUUAAUUAUAAAUACCUAUAUAUAGGAGUAGGAUUUUCUCUCACCCAACCCUACUUUAAUCAUUAUCACUUAAGUGUAAACCUCCACCUCCCCCUCUUUCCCUUUACCGAAAAAAAAUGCACUUUAAUUCCUAAGGAGAGUGGCUGUUCCUGGCCCUGAAACCAGAUUACUUCAGGAGGAGAGUUAAGGAGGGAGAGCUCUUACCAGACCCUGUGAAAUGAACCAAAUUUCUUAAUGUAAACACACAAGUAAUAACAUCCACUUUUAAGUGGCCCCCACUCCAUGCCAAAGGGAAAAAGAACCGCCAAAUUGAAAAAGGGUUCUAAAUACCUGUCCUGAUUUUGGAAGUUUCACUGGGGAAAAACUACCUAAGAUUAUUUUCACAGCUACCAAUUUGUCAGAAACUUUGGUGGUGUUUUGUGGGAGGCUGAGAUUUUUUAAAUUAAAAAUCAAGUGAAAACACAAAGACUCUAAGACACGAUCCUGAUUUGUGUCAUUUCUAAGUAUCAGAUUUGUUCUCCCUUCAUUUGACAGGUGUUCUCAGUCUCUCCUCCUGUAAGAUUCUGUCCUUCCCCUGAUGACAAGCCAAUAGUUCUUGGUGGGGUUGCAUGUCUCCUAGAGCCCCAGGACCCCUGUCGUGUCGGGGAAGGGGGGAGGGCAGGAGGGUGGGCAGAGACUCGGGUUGGGGGAGGGAGUUCAAAGAAAGAGUGAAAAUAUGGGUUUAUAUAAACAUAUUUAAAGCAGUUUAGCAAAAGCUUUCUCGUUGAACAGCUUUAAGAACAAUGUGAAUGAAAUCUUAGCAACUUGGUUAGUAAUCUGAAAAGUCUAUUAAUGUAUACUUGAAAUUCUGUUUGUAUAAAAAUGCAUUUUCCCCUUUAUUUUAACACUGUGUAAAAGAACAUUAUGCAUGUGAGUGGUUUGAGAAUUAAAUGGUUUAAUACUCA